GUAUUUUACAAACUGAGAAAGUAGCUCCAGCAGCACCCGAGAGGGUCAGGAGAAAAGCGGAGGAAGCUGGGUAGGCCCUGAGGGGCCUCGGUAAGCCAUCAUGACCACCCGGCAAGCCACGAAGGAUCCCCUCCUCCGGGGUGUAUCUCCUACCCCUAGCAAGAUUCCGGUACGCUCUCAGAAACGCACGCCUUUCCCCACUGUUACAUCGUGCGCCGUGGACCAGGAGAACCAAGAUCCAAGGAGAUGGGUGCAGAAACCACCGCUCAAUAUUCAACGCCCCCUCGUUGAUUCAGCAGGCCCCAGGCCGAAAGCCAGGCACCAGGCAGAGACAUCACAAAGAUUGGUGGGGAUCAGUCAGCCUCGGAACCCCUUGGAAGAGCUCAGGCCUAGCCCUAGGGGUCAAAAUGUGGGGCCUGGGCCCCCUGCCCAGACAGAGGCUCCAGGGACCAUAGAGUUUGUGGCUGACCCUGCAGCCCUGGCCACCAUCCUGUCAGGUGAGGGUGUGAAGAGCUGUCACCUGGGGCGCCAGCCUAGUCUGGCUAAAAGAGUACUGGUUCGAGGAAGUCAGGGAGGCACCACCCAGAGGGUCCAGGGUGUUCGGGCCUCUGCAUAUUUGGCCCCCAGAACCCCCACCCACCGACUGGACCCUGCCAGGGCUUCCUGCUUCUCUAGGCUGGAGGGACCAGGACCUCGAGGCCGGACAUUGUGCCCCCAGAGGCUACAGGCUCUGAUUUCACCUUCAGGACCUUCCUUUCACCCUUCCACUCGCCCCAGUUUCCAGGAGCUAAGAAGGGAGACAGCUGGCAGCAGCCGGACUUCAGUGAGCCAGGCCUCAGGAUUGCUCCUGGAGACCCCAGUCCAGCCUGCUUUCUCUCUUCCUAAAGGAGAACGCGAGGUUGUCACUCACUCAGAUGAAGGAGGUGUGGCCUCUCUUGGUCUGGCCCAGCGAGUACCAUUAAGAGAAAACCGAGAAAUGUCACAUACCAGGGACAGCCAUGACUCCCACCUGAUGCCCUCCCCUGCCCCUGUGGCCCAGCCCUUGCCUGGCCAUGUGGUGCCAUGUCCAUCACCCUUUGGACGGGCUCAGCGUGUACCCUCCCCAGGCCCUCCAACUCUGACCUCAUAUUCAGUGUUGCGGCGUCUCACCGUUCAACCUAAAACCCGGUUCACACCCAUGCCAUCAACCCCCAGAGUUCAGCAGGCCCAGUGGCUGCGUGGUGUCUCCCCUCAGUCCUGCUCUGAAGAUCCUGCCCUGCCCUGGGAGCAGGUUGCCGUCCGGUUGUUUGACCAGGAGAGUUGUAUAAGGUCACUGGAGGGUUCUGGGAAACCACCGGUGGCCACUCCUUCUGGACCCCACUCUAACAGAACCCCCAGCCUCCAGGAGGUGAAGAUUCAACGCAUCGGUAUCCUGCAACAGCUGUUGAGACAGGAAGUAGAGGGGCUGGUAGGGGGCCAGUGUGUCCCUCUUAAUGGAGGCUCUUCUCUGGAUAUGGUUGAACUUCAGCCCCUGCUGACUGAGAUUUCUAGAACUCUGAAUGCCACAGAGCAUAACUCUGGGACUUCCCACCUUCCUGGACUGUUAAAACACUCAGGGCUGCCAAAGCCCUGUCUUCCAGAGGAGUGCGGGGAACCACAGCCCUGCCCUCCGGCAGAGCCUGGGCCCCCAGAGGCCUUCUGUAGGAGUGAGCCUGAGAUACCAGAGCCCUCCCUCCAGGAACAGCUUGAAGUACCAGAGCCCUACCCUCCAGCAGAACCCAGGCCCCUAGAGUCCUGCUGUAGGAGUGAGCCUGAGAUACCGGAGUCCUCUCGCCAGGAACAGCUUGAGGUACCUGAGCCCUGCCCUCCAGCAGAACCCAGGCCCCUAGAGUCCUACUGUAGGAUUGAGCCUGAGAUACCGGAGUCCUCUCGCCAGGAACAGCUUGAGGUACCUGAGCCCUGCCCUCCAGCAGAACCCGGGCCCCUUCAGCCCAGCACCCAGGGGCAGUCUGGACCCCCAGGGCCCUGCCCUAGGGUAGAGCUGGGGGCAUCAGAGCCCUGCACCCUGGAACAUAGAAGUCUAGAGUCCAGUCUACCACCCUGCUGCAGUCAGUGGGCUCCAGCAACCACCAGCCUGAUCUUCUCUUCCCAACACCCGCUUUGUGCCAGCCCCCCUAUCUGCUCACUCCAGUCUUUGAGACCCCCAGCAGGCCAGGCAGGUAAGGAGUUGGCUGGGAAGGAGUGUGAACACAAGAGGUCCUCACCUCACUGUGAGCUGCACACCUGCCCUGCCCCUACCCCAGGCAAUCUCAUGCUUCCACACCUUCCACCCUGGCCCAGCCUGGCUCUCCCUCAGGAAGAGGGGAGGGGCUGCACUUCCAGCCCUGUGCUCCUAAUUGGCUUGGCCGUUGGUGGGGGAGGAGGAGAGGACAGUACAUGGUGGAAGUAUAGGACCCCAGACCUCCCUCUAAAUUUUCCAUGCCCCUCAGGCCUCAGCAAUCUGGCCCCUCGAACCCUAGCCCUGAGGGAGCGCCUCAAAUCGUGUUUAACCGCCAUCCACUGCUUCCACGAGGCUCGUCUGGACGAUGAGUGUGCCUUUUACACCAGCCGAGCCCCUCCCUCAGGCCCCACCCGGGUCUGCACCAACCCUGUGGCUACAUUACUCGAAUGGCAGGAUGCCCUGUGUUUCAUUCCAGUUGGUUCUGCUGCCCCCCAGGGCUCUCCAUGAUGAGACAACCACUCCUGCCCUGCCGUACUUCUUCCUUUUAGCCCUUAUUUAUUGUCGGUCUGCCCAUGGGACUGGGAGCCGCCCACUUUUGUCCUCAAUAAAGUUUCUAAAGUA